AAGUCUCCUCCGCGGCGCGGAGCCGCGAUGUCUCCGGCGGCUGCGGCGGCUGGAGCAGGCGAGCGGCGGCGGCCGAUAGCGAGUGUCAGGGCCGGCCGGGGCGGCGCUUCUCGGCCUGUCGCUGGUCGGCCUCCUACUGUACCUCGUGCCUGCUGCGGCUGCGCUGGCCUGGCUGGCCGUGGGGACUACCGCGGCCUGGUGGGGACUGAGCCGCGAGCCCCGAGGUUCGCGCCCCUUGUCCUCCUUCGUUCAGAAGGCGCGACAUCGGCGAACACUGUUCGCUUCGCCUCCGGCCAAGUCGACAGCCAACGGAAACCUCCUAGAGCCGCGGACCCUGCUCGAAGGACCUGACCCUGCCGAACUGCUCCUCAUGGGCAGUUACCUGGGCAAGCCCGGGCCGCCGCAGCCCGCCCCCGCUCCGGAGGGCCAGGACCUGCGGAAUAGGCCUGGCCGCCGCCCGCCCGCCCGGCGCCGCGCUCCACACCGCCCUCCCCGCCGACCCAUCGCGUUCACCACUUUUACCCCUCUCUCCCCACUCCUCUUCUCCGACCCUCCGGGAGGCCUUCCCCACGGGAUCGUGGGACUUUACCAGAUCGGUUUGUAAUAACACCUCGAAGACGCUAUCCGAUCCAUCAGGCCCAGUAUUCCUGUCCGGGGGUACUUCCCACAGUGUGCUGGAAUGGUUAUCACAAGAAGGCUGUGCUGUCCCCUCGCAACUCCAGGAUGGUGUGUAGCCCAGUGACUCUGAGGAUCGCCCCUCCUGACAGAAGAUUUUCGCGUUCUGCGAUACCAGAGCAGAUAAUCAGCUCAACACUGUCCUCACCAUCAAGUAAUGCCCCAGACCCAUGUGCAAAGGAGACUGUACUGAGUGCCCUCAAAGAGAAGAAGAAGAAAAGGACAGUGGAGGAAGAAGACCAAAUAUUCCUUGAUGGCCAGGAAAAUAAAAGAAGCUGUCUUGUCGACGGUCUCACUGAUGCCUCUUCUGCAUUCAAAGUUCCUCGACCCGGGCCAGAUACACUCCAGUUCACAGUGGAUGUCUUCCACUUUGCUAAUGACUCCAGAAACAUGAUAUACAUCACCUGCCACCUGAAGGUCACCCUAGCUGAGCAGGACCCAGAUGAACUCAACAAGGCCUGUUCCUUCAGCAAGCCUUCCAACAGCUGGUUCCCAGUGGAAGGCCUGGCUGACAUCUGUCAAUGCUGUAACAAAGGUGACUGUGGCACUCCAAGCCAUUCCAGGAGGCAGCCUCGUGUCGUGAGCCAGUGGUCCACGUCUGCUUCCCUGUAACCGCAGGCAUGUGACAGAAGAAGCAGAUGUCACCGUGGGGCCACUGAUCUUCCUGGACAGGAGGGGUGACCAUGAAGUAGAGCAGUGGGCUUUGCCUUCUGACACCUCAGUGGUGCUGCUGGGCGUAGGCCUGGCUGUGGUGGUGUCCCUGACUCUGACUGCUGUUAUCCUGGUUCUCACCAGGAGGUGUCGCACUGCCUCCCACCCUGUGUCUGCUUCCGAAUAAAAGAAGAAAGCAAUA